AGACCUGGCGGCCGGACCGACCCGCGCCUGGCGGAUGCGCCCGGCGCGCCCACAGCAGCCCCCGCGCCCGCCGUGCCGCCGCCGGGACGUGGGGCCCUUGGGCCGUCGGGCCGCCUGGGGAGCGCCAGCCCGGAUCCGGCUGCCCAGAUGCGGGCGCCACUCUGCCUGCUCCUGCUCGUCGCCCACGCCGUGGACAUGCUCGCCCUGAACCGAAGGAAGAAGCAAGUGGGCACUGGCCUGGGGGGCAACUGCACAGGCUGUAUCAUCUGCUCAGAGGAGAACGGCUGUUCCACCUGCCAGCAGAGGCUCUUCCUGUUCAUCCGCCGGGAAGGCAUCCGCCAGUACGGCAAGUGCCUGCACGACUGUCCCCCUGGGUACUUCGGCAUCCGCGGCCAGGAGGUCAACAGGUGCAAAAAAUGUGGGGCCACUUGUGAGAGCUGCUUCAGCCAGGACUUCUGCAUCCGGUGCAAGAGGCAGUUUUACUUGUACAAGGGGAAGUGUCUGCCCACCUGCCCGCCGGGCACUUUGGCCCACCAGAACACACGGGAGUGCCAGGGGGAGUGUGAACUGGGUCCCUGGGGCGGCUGGAGCCCCUGCACACACAAUGGAAAGACCUGCGGCUCGGCUUGGGGCCUGGAGAGCCGGGUACGAGAGGCUGGCCGGGCUGGGCAUGAGGAGGCAGCCACCUGCCAGGUGCUUUCUGAGUCAAGGAAAUGUCCCAUCCAGAGGCCCUGCCCAGGAGAGAGGAGCCCCGGCCAGAAGAAGGGCAGGAAGGACCGGCGCCCACGCAAGGACAGGAAGCUGGACCGCAGGCUGGACGUGAGGCCGCGCCAGCCCGGCCUGCAGCCCUGACCGCCGGCUCUCCCGACUCUCUGGUCCUAGUCCUCGGCCCCUGCACACCUCCUCCUGCUCCUUCUCCUCCUCUCCUCUUACUCUUUCUCCUCUGUCUUCUCCAUUUGUCCUCUCUUUCUUUCCACCCUUCUAUCAUUUUUCUGUCAGUCUACCUUCCCUUUCUUUUUCUUUUUUAUUUCCUUUAUUUCUUCCACCUCCAUUCUCCUCUCCUUUCUCCCUCCCUCCUUCCCUUCCUUCCUCUUCUUUCUCACUUAUCUUUUAUCUUUCCUUUUCUUUCUUCCUGUGUUUCUUCCUGUCCUUCACCGCAUCCUUCUCUCUCUCCCUCCUCUUGUCUCCCUCUCACACACACUUUAAGAGGGACCAUGAGCCUGUGCCCUCCCCUGCAGCUUUCUCUAUCUACAACUUAAAGAAAGCAAACAUCUUUUCCCAGGCCUUUCCCUGACCCCAUCUUUGCAGAGAAAGGGUUUCCAGAGGGCAAAGCUGGGACACAGCACAGGUGAAUCCUGAAGGCCCUGCUUCUGCUCUGGGGGAGGCUCCAGGACCCUGAGCUGUGAGCACCUGGUUCUCUGGACAGUCCCCAGAGGCCAUUUCCACAGCCUUCAGCCACCAGCCACCCCGAGGAGCUGGCUGGACAAGGCUCCAGGGCUUCCAGAGGCCUGGCUUGGACACCUCCCCCAGCUGGCCGUGGAGGGUCACAACCUGGCCUCUGGGUGGGCAGCCAGCCCUGGAGGGCAUCCUCUGCAAGCUGCCUGCCACCCUCAUCGGCACUCCCCCACAGGCCUCCCUCUCAUGGGUUCCAUGCCCCUUUUUCCCAAGCCGGAUCAGGUGAGCUGUCACUGCUGGGGGAUCCACCUGCCCAGCCCAGAAGAGGCCACUGAAACGGAAAGGAAAGCUGAGAUUAUCCAGCAGCUCUGUUCCCCACCUCAGCGCUUCCUGCCCAUGUGGGGAAACAGGUCUGAGAAGGAAGGGGCUUGCCCAGGGUCACACAGGAAGCCUUCAGGCUCUGCUUCUGCCUGAUGGCUCUGCUCAGCACAUUCACGGUGGAGAGGAGAAUUUGGGGGUCACUUGAGGGGGGAAAUGUAGGGAAUUGUGGGUGGGGAGCAAGGGAAGAUCCGUGCACUCGUCCACACCCACCACCACACUCGCUGACACCCACCCCCACACGCUGACACCCACCCCCACACUUGCCCACACCCAUCACCGCACUCGCCCACACCCACCACCACACUGCCCCACACCCACCACCACACUCCCCCACACCCACCACCACACUCGCCCACACCCACCACCAGUGACUUGAGCAUCUGUGCUUCGCUGUGACGCCCCUCGCCCUAGGCAGGAACGACGCUGGGAGGAGUCUCCAGGUCAGACCCAGCUUGGAAGCAAGUCUGUCCUCACUGCCUAUCCUUCUGCCAUCAUAACACCCCCUUCCUGCUCUGCUCCCCGGAAUCCUCAGAAACGGGAUUUGUAUUUGCCGUGACUGGUUGGCCUGAACACGUAGGGCUCCGUGACUGGGACAGGAAUGGGCAGGAGAAGCAAGAGUCGGAGCUCCAAGGGGCCCAGGGGUGGCCUGGGGAAGGAAGAUGGUCAGCAGGCUGGGGGAGAGGCUCUAGGUGAUGAAAUAUUACAUUCCCGACCCCAAGAGAGCACCCACCCUCAGACCUGCCCUCCACCUGGCAGCUGGGGAGCCCUGGCCUGAACCCCCCCCUCCCAGCAGGCCCACCCUCUCUCUGACUUCCCUGCUCUCACCUCCCCGAGAACAGCUAGAGCCCCCUCCUCCGCCUGGCCAGGCCACCAGCUUCUCUUCUGCAAACGUUUGUGCCUCUGAAAUGCUCCGUUGUUAUUGUUUCAAGACCCUAACUUUUUUUUAAAACUUUCUUAAUAAAGGGAAAAGAAACUUGUAAA